ACUUUUACAUUUUUGUCUUCAUUGCUUAACAUCGUUUUUAAGAAUUCAAAAUGUCCGGACGCGGCAAGCAAGGCGGAAAGGCCCGAGCUAAGGCUAAGACCCGCUCUUCGCGGGCCGGACUCCAGUUCCCUGUGGGCCGCGUACACCGCUUGCUCCGCAAGGGCAACUACUCCGAGCGAGUCGGGGCCGGCGCGCCAGUGUAUCUGGCGGCGGUGUUGGAGUACCUGACCGCCGAGAUCCUGGAGCUGGCGGGCAACGCCGCCCGCGACAACAAGAAGACCCGCAUCAUCCCCCGACACCUGCAGCUGGCCAUCCGCAACGACGAGGAGCUAAACAAGUUGCUGGGUAAAGUCACAAUUGCUCAGGGCGGUGUUCUGCCCAACAUCCAGGCUGUACUGCUCCCCAAGAAGACUGAGAGUCACCACAAGGCCAAGGGCAAGUAAAACGAGAACUCUUAUAUUGGCUUUUUAAGGAAGCAGUCUUAACAAAGGCUCUUUUCAGAGCCACCCA